ACAGCGAGGUCGGCAGCGGCACAGCGAGGUCGGCAGCGGCACAGCGAGGUCGGCAGCGGCACAGCGAGGUCGGCAGCGGCAGCGAGGUCGGCAGCGGCACAGCGAGGUCGGCAGCGGCAGCGAGGUCGGCAGCGGCGCGCGCUGUGCUCUUCCGCGGACUCUGAAUCAUGGCGACCACGGCCACGAUGGCGACCUCGGGCUCGGCGCGAAAGCGGCUGCUCAAAGAGGAAGACAUGACUAAAGUGGAAUUCGAGACCAGCGAGGAGGUGGAUGUGACCCCCACGUUCGACACCAUGGGCCUGCGGGAGGACCUGCUGCGGGGCAUCUACGCUUACGGUUUUGAAAAACCAUCAGCAAUCCAGCAACGAGCAAUCAAGCAGAUCAUCAAAGGGAGAGAUGUCAUCGCACAGUCUCAGUCCGGCACAGGAAAAACAGCCACCUUCAGUAUCUCAGUCCUCCAGUGUUUGGAUAUUCAGGUUCGUGAAACUCAAGCUUUGAUCUUGGCUCCCACAAGAGAGUUGGCUGUGCAGAUCCAGAAGGGGCUGCUUGCUCUCGGUGACUACAUGAAUGUCCAGUGCCAUGCCUGCAUUGGAGGCACCAAUGUUGGCGAGGACAUCAGGAAGCUGGAUUACGGACAGCAUGUUGUCGCGGGCACUCCAGGGCGUGUUUUUGAUAUGAUUCGUCGCAGAAGCCUAAGGACACGUGCUAUCAAAAUGUUGGUUUUGGAUGAAGCUGAUGAAAUGUUGAAUAAAGGUUUCAAAGAGCAGAUUUACGAUGUAUACAGGUACCUGCCUCCAGCCACACAGGUGGUUCUCAUCAGUGCCACGCUGCCACACGAGAUUCUGGAGAUGACCAACAAGUUCAUGACCGACCCAAUCCGCAUCUUGGUGAAACGUGAUGAAUUGACUCUGGAAGGCAUCAAGCAAUUUUUCGUGGCAGUGGAGAGGGAAGAGUGGAAAUUUGACACUCUGUGUGACCUCUACGACACACUGACCAUCACUCAGGCGGUCAUCUUCUGCAACACCAAAAGAAAGGUGGACUGGCUGACGGAGAAAAUGAGGGAAGCCAACUUCACUGUAUCCUCAAUGCAUGGAGACAUGCCCCAGAAAGAGCGGGAGUCCAUCAUGAAGGAGUUCCGGUCGGGCGCCAGCCGAGUGCUUAUUUCUACAGAUGUCUGGGCCAGGGGGUUGGAUGUCCCUCAGGUGUCCCUCAUCAUUAACUAUGAUCUCCCUAAUAACAGAGAAUUGUACAUACACAGAAUUGGGAGAUCAGGUCGAUACGGCCGGAAGGGUGUGGCCAUUAACUUUGUAAAGAAUGACGACAUCCGCAUCCUCAGAGAUAUCGAGCAGUACUAUUCCACUCAGAUUGAUGAGAUGCCGAUGAACGUUGCUGAUCUUAUCUGAAGCAGCAGAUCAGUGGGAUGAGGGAGACUGUUCACCUGCUGUGUACUCCUGUUUGGAAGUAUUUAGAUCCAGAUUCUACUUAAUGGGGUUUAUAUGGACUUUCUUCUCAUAAAUGGCCUGCCGUCUCCCUUCCUUUGAAGAGGAUAUGGGGAUUCUGCUCUCUUUUCUUAUUUACAUGUAAAUAAUACAUUGUUCUAAGUCUUUUUCAUUAAAAAUUUAAAACUUUUCCCAUAAACUCUAUACUUCUAAGGUGCCACCACCUUCUCUAGUAACUUACUGUGUAGUCUUGGGUCAUUUCACUCACUUUUCUUUUUUUCUUUUCUUUUUCUUUUUUUUUUUUGAGACAGUCUCCCUCUGUUGCCCAGGCAGGAGCGCAGUGGCGUGAUCUCCUCUCACCGCAAGCUCCACUUCCUGGGUUCAUGCCAUUCUCCUACCUCAGCCUCCCACGUAGCUGGGAGUACAGGCGGCCGCCACCAUGCCAGGCUAAUUUUUUUGUAUUUUCAGUAGAGACGGGGUUUCACCGUGUUAGCCAAGAUGGUCUCGAUCUCCUGACCUCGUGAUCCACCCACCUCGGCCUCCCAAAGUGCUGGGAUUACAGGCGUGAGCCACUGCACCCGGCCCAUUUCACUCACUUUUCUAAUCUUUUUUUUUGGAAAGAGUUUCAUCGUUGAUGAGUUUUGCUCUGCUGCCCAGGCUGAAGAGCAGUGGCACCAUCACAACUCAUUGCAGCCACAACCUCCUGGGCUCAAGCGAUCCUCUCACCUCACCCUCCUGAGUAGCUGGGACUACAGGUGCAUGCCAGCACAUCUGGCUAAUAUUUAAAUUUUUUGUAGAGACAGGGUCUCACUUUGUGGCCUAGGCUGGUCUGUCACUCAUGGGUUUAAGUGAUUCUCCCAUCUUGGCCUUACAAAGUGCUGGGAUAACAGGUGUGAGCCACCAUGCCUGGCCUCAUUUUUCUAAUUUUUUUUUUUUGUUGUUUUUUUGAGAGCCCAGGAUCUCCCUGUCGCCCAGGCAGGAGUAUAGUGGCAGGAUCAUGACUUACCACAAUGUUGACAAACUAAAACAGAUAAUUAUCUGUUUAAAUAUUUAAAUUAUUAAAGUAUUUAAGUUAUCUGUUGAAA